AGUGCUCAGAGGGUCUGUGGUCAUGGUGAGAAGAACCCCGCAGCUCCUGGAAGGGCGAGAGGACCCGGAGAGGCUUCCUCUGCCAGACUCAGCUGUGCUUUGAGGAGGGGAAGUGACCCAAGGCCAGCCCAGCCGUGGUCCUGGGAGGCAGCAUCGCCCGGUUAGGGCUUCCUGCGUGUCACCGGGGGCCUUGCUCUGGUUUCUGGCUGAACUUGUUGGGCACUGGGCGAUCCUAGUGGGGGUUCUGCUCGCUGGAGCGAGAGGACCCUCUGGGGCGUGGGACCGGCGGUGGCCUGGACGUCAGCAGAGGAGGAAAGUCCUGCUUCAGGCAGCCAUUCAGGGAGGGACAGGAAUCACCCGAGAGUGACCUGCCAGCAGCAGGGGCGGCCCUCCUGCUCUGUUUGUGUCCGCAGCACGUGGUCAGUGCCUGGCACUGGAAACAGUAGCUCAGCAAAUAUUUGUCCGUCAAAGGAGUACGGGGGCCGGACCACCCAGUUCCGGCCCCUCCUCUGCAGACCAGGAAAUGGAGCCAUUUGCCGCAGGGGAGACGUUCUCUUCCAGAUGGCUGAAGUCCACAGGCAGAUCCAGAAUCAGCUGGAAGAAAUGCUGAAGUCUUUUCACAACGAGCUGCUUACGCAGCUGGAGCAGAAGGUGGAGCUGGACUCCAGGUAUCUGAGUGCUGCGCUGAAGAAAUACCAGACUGAGCAAAGGAGCAAAGGCGACGCCCUGGACAAGUGUCAGGCUGAGCUGAAGAAGCUUCGGAAGAAGAGCCAGGGCAGCAAGAAUCCUCAGAAGUACUCGGACAAGGAGCUGCAGUACAUCGACGCCAUCAGCAACAAGCAGGGCGAGCUGGAGAAUUACGUGUCCGACGGCUACAAGACCGCACUGACAGAGGAGCGCAGGCGCUUCUGCUUCCUGGUGGAGAAGCAGUGCGCCGUGGCCAAGAACUCCGCGGCCUACCACUCCAAGGGCAAGGAGCUGCUGGCGCAGAAGCUGCCGCUGUGGCAACAGGCCUGUGCCGACCCCAGCAAGAUCCCGGAGCGCGCGGUGCAGCUCAUGCAGCAGGUGGCCAGCAACGGCGCCACCCUCCCCAGCGCCCUGUCGGCCUCCAAGUCCAACCUGGUCAUUUCCGACCCCAUUCCGGGGGCCAAGCCCCUGCCGGUGCCCCCCGAGCUGGCACCGUUCGUGGGGCGGAUGUCUGCCCAGGAGAGCACACCCAUCAUGAACGGCGUCACAGGCCCGGAUGGCGAGGACUACAGCCCGUGGGCUGACCGCAAGGCUGCCCAGCCCAAAUCCCUGUCUCCUCCGCAGUCUCAGAGCAAGCUCAGCGACUCCUACUCCAACACACUCCCCGUGCGCAAGAGCGUGACCCCAAAAAACAGCUAUGCCACCACAGCCGAGAACAAGACUCUGCCUCGCUCGAGCUCCAUGGCAGCCGGCCUGGAGCGCAAUGGCCGUAUGCGGGUGAAGGCCAUCUUCUCCCACGCUGCUGGGGACAACAGCACCCUCCUGAGCUUCAAGGAGGGUGACCUCAUUACCCUGCUGGUGCCUGAGGCCCGCGAUGGCUGGCACUACGGAGAGAGUGAGAAGACCAAGAUGCGGGGCUGGUUUCCCUUCUCCUACACCCGGGUCUUGGACAGCGAUGGCAGUGACAGGCUGCACAUGAGCCUGCAGCAAGGGAAGAGCAGCAGCACGGGCAACCUCCUGGACAAGGACGACCUGGCCAUCCCACCCCCCGAUUACGGCGCCGCCUCCCGGGCCUUCCCCGCCCAGACGGCCAGCGGCUUCAAGCAGAGGCCCUACAGUGUGGCCGUGCCCGCCUUCUCCCAGGGCCUGGAUGACUAUGGAGCGCGGUCCAUGAGCAGGAAUCCCUUUGCCCACGUCCAGCUGAAGCCGACAGUGACCAACGACAGGUCUGCCCCCCUCCUCAGCUGAUGGCCACAUCUGCAGUGCUGCCCAUCUGGUGGCUUCCCCCGCCCUUCCCAUGUAGCCUGUUCUGUCAUCAUCUGUGCGUUCCUGUGUAGAGAACAUCCAGGCCCCGGCUGCCUGGUCUUGCCCCACUUGAGUCUGGCCUGGACUGGAUCCCAGCUGUUCUAGGCAGGGCCGGGCAGAGUGGGGCGCAGGCCCCUGAAGGGCGAGACCCAGUGGCUGGGCUGCCCAGGGCUGAGGGGCCGCCUCUUGAGGGUACACGCCUCUGGUCACAUGGCCAUGGAGCCUUGGGUACCCCUGAGUUAAGGGAGGACAUUUGGCCAGCUGGUGGCUGGGAGGGGAGCCUGGCUGCCCUGCUGCUUCUCCUGCCUAAUAAACAGGCUUCUCCUGCACCAGGUGUGAUCUGUCCGCCCAAGGGCCAGAAGGCCGGGAGCACGGGGAUGGGAGCGCCCGCACCCUGGCUGGAAGAUGAACUUCCCGUAAGCACGUAAUUCCCUGCAGGUCCGGCAGCUACACCUGGAGUGUGGGGCCUGGUCCCUCCCCAUGCCCCUCGGUGGGGCUCUCCUGGGCCCCUCACUCCCACUGGCAAUGUCACAAGGGCCUCCCCAGGCCCCUCCUGCCUCGGGCAGGCCCCAGCCCUCCUCCUUACCCAACCUCCCAUCCAGAACCUUGCUGCCAGGGCCUCCCAGCUCGCUCCUGCGGCCAAAGGCCAGCUGUCAGGUGCUAUGCGGGGUCACCAGCAGAGUGCCCGCUGGCAGGUGGGGGCUUCCCCGCUUCCGGGGUCUGCCCCAGGACUCCUGGGUGGACCUCCCCCCCCCACCUCCGCUGACUCCUGCAGGCACUGGGGAGCUCUGCUGGAAUUGGGGGUUUUAAAACUUCAUUAGCAGAUUUGUGCUCUUCCAUACUGUUUGUUUGUUUGUUAGGUGAAAUACAGUGUGGUGAGCUGCACUGGUGACAACAGCCCUUACCUGGCUGGGGAGGUGUCUCCAGCAGAGCUCACUCCCGCCUACAGCCACUCACACCCCGGGGACAGGAAGCUGUAGAGUUGGCGGGCCAGGAGGGCAGUUGAGAGCUGGCCAGCGGAGGGUGCAGGGAAGCCCAGCUGUGCUCAACUCUCCUGCCUCCGCCUUCCACCCUGGGCCCAGGGACAGACAGACAUUGCCCUCAGAAGGGCAGGGAGGAGGCUGUCCUGGAGAGGCCUGUAGGUCCAUUCUUCACCCGUCCCUACCAGGCCAACUCGGCCUGCAGGAAGGGAGACCUGCAGGGCGCUACCCCUGCGCCCCCACACACAGUAGGGCCAGAACACCAUCCCCUCCACCGGGGUGUGCCGAGGACAGUGGGGAGGAGAGGAGAGGGGCAGCUUCCUCCUGGCCCCAGGAAGGGCUGGCAUCGGGUUCCUGGCACAGCCCCUCCUGUCCAGGACUUUAUCAUCGGCAGACCUCAGAAGACAACACACAAAGGUUUCUUUUGUCUUAGCUUCAUUUCUCUUAAAAAACAAGGAACAAGAAAACAUUGCACCAGCGUUCUAAGCCUCAAACAAAACACAAAACAAAUCCCCCUGCGAAGCAACAAUAAACUUUACAUCUCUUUGGCAACAAUAA